CCUGUAGAGACAAGAAGACAGUAAUGAGGGGCCUUGAGUCUGUCUUCUUCUUUUUUUUUUUUUCUUGAGAUGGAAUCUCGCUUUGUCACCCAGGCUGGAGUGCAAUGGCACGAUCUCGGCUUACUGCAACCUCCGCCUCCCAGGUUCAAGCGAUUCUCCUGUCUCAGCCUCCCGAGUAGCUGGGAUUACAGGCACACCGCCACCAUGACUGGCUAACUUUUUGUAUUUUAGUAGUGACGGGGUUUCACUGUGUUACCCAGGCUGGUCUCGAACUCCUGACCUCAGGCAAUCCAGUUCCUUCAGGCAACCUUCCAAGGAAAUGGUUUCCAGGCUCUUCCCUAUCCUGAAUGUACCGUUGAACUUGGCCCAGUUUGUCACUGUUCUCUGCUGGGCCUUGAUUUGGGUAUAGAACUCCAGGUGGCCUGGGCAGUACAGGCAAAAGCAGGACUAUUCAUUCUUAUUCCUGGCUGUUAGACCUCUGUUGAGGCAGCCUGAGCUGCUAUUAGCUGUUUCUGCACAGGUACAGGCUGAACAUCGAUAUCUCAUAUUCAGGCUUGUUGAGAUCUCUUUUGUAUCCUGCUUCUGUCAUCAUAGGAUUUAGCCAUUUCUCCAGUGAGGCCCAACAAGCCCUCUCAGUCCUGCUCUAACAAAAAACGGCCAGACCCCUUUUUGCUUUCUCUCUUUCCCUUAUUGGAAACCUGCCUAUGACCCUGGAUACAACUCUCAGGAAGGUCCCUGCCCCCAUCACUGGCAAAGAAGCUACUGCCAGCUGACCUCAGCCACUAUCACUUCUUCCCUUUGCAGAGUGUUCUAGGAUUUAUGACAUAUGCUUGUUGAUCCUGGGAAGGAUGUGUGCCUGGGCAGGCGUGGAGAAUUGGGUACUGUGGGCGGGAGGGCAGGCCCUGAGGAGCAGGGGGUGGGAUCCUCCAGUCUUAGAAUAGUCCCAGUCUGGCUACAACCUUCAACCCAAGACCCGGAUUCUUCAGCACCGAGUGCCACGCCCUGCAGGAUGUUCUCUGCGGCCUCCCAGCCUUUGGACCCCGAUGGGACCUUGUUCCGGCUUCGCUUCACAGCCAUGGUCUGGUGGGCCAUCACUUUUCCUGUGUUCGGCUUCUUCUUCUGCAUCAUCUGGUCCCUGGUGUUCCACUUUGAGUACACGGUGGCCACUGACUGUGGGGUGCCCAAUUACCUGCCCUCGGUGAGCUCAGCCAUCGGCGGGGAGGUGCCCCAGCGCUACGUGUGGCGUUUCUGCAUCGGCCUGCACUCGGCGCCUCGCUUCUUGGUGGCCUUCGCCUACUGGAACCACUACCUCAGCUGCACCUCCCCGUGUUCCUGCUAUCGCCCGCUCUGCCGCCUCAACUUCGGCCUCAAUGUCGUGGAGAACCUCGCGUUGCUAGUGCUCACUUAUGUCUCCUCCUCCGAGGACUUCACCAUCCACGAAAAUGCUUUCAUUGUGUUCAUUGCCUCAUCCCUCGGGCACAUGCUCCUCACCUGCAUUCUCUGGCGGUUGACCAAGAAGCACACAGUAAGUCAGGAGGAUCGCAAGUCCUACAGCUGGAAACAGCGGCUCUUCAUCAUCAACUUCAUCUCCUUCUUCUCGGCGCUGGCUGUCUACUUUCGGCACAACAUGUAUUGUGAGGCUGGAGUGUACACCAUCUUUGCCAUCCUGGAGUACACUGUUGUCUUAACCAACAUGGCGUUCCACAUGACGGCCUGGUGGGACUUCGGGAACAAGGAGCUGCUCAUAACCUCUCAGCCUGAGGAAAAGCGAUUCUGAACCCUUCAGUCCUGCUUGGGAGGACGCAGCCCACUGCCCAGAAACAAGAAACACGAUACCAUUCUGGCCUUCCCCACCCCACAUCCUCUCUUGGCCUUACUGAAGAUGGGGGAAGGGUAAGAAGGAAGGGUGUAGGCCAAGGCUCACCCCAGUGCUGCUGGCUUCUCCUCUCCACCCCUCAUAUGGGCGUGGGGUCCUCAAACAUCACCUUUACCUGAGAGGCCCCAAGAAGCUGAGCUGGCAGAGAGCUCCACCAUUUGGUGCUAAAAAAAAAAACGUCCUGAGGUUCAUGACCACCAUCCAGUUUCUGGCCUUUACACAGUCACCUUUCACUGAGGUCAGGAGCCCCUGAGCAGUGGCUGCUCCCUGACAACCACAGCCAUUUCUCUGCACGGGGGUCAUUCAUAGGACUAAUGUAUUUCAUGAUCUACUGUGCACAUCCAGGCCUGUGGCCACAGUCCCCUGCUAAAGUUGCUCAGGUGUUCUAGUCCUGACUUCACCUUUUUGAUUUGGUGUGUGCCCUAGGGUAUGUACCCUUCCCCAUCUGAGCCUCGGUGUGUCCAUGUGUCUGGCGGGGGAUGGGUGGACUGUAUGAUUUCCAAGGACUCUACCAGUCAGUGGUUCUGAUGUCAUCGGGUGGAGGUGGUGUUCUAUACCUAAAGGAUGACCUGCUCCAGAAACAGCACCAGCACAGCAUGUAUUUUCUUCUCUUCUGAAAGUUCUGGCUUGUAGACCCCUCCCCUCCUUUGCAAAGGUAUGGGAUAGAGGGGUCAGAUGCAGAUCUCUACUGUAAAAUGGGCUCCCUGGUAUCUCCUGUCUUCCCUACUGCUCCAAACCCUAAAUUUUGGUUGUACAUUUUAUUUGAAAGGAAAAUAAAUUUUUUUUUUGGGCCAACAGUUGCCUAGGCUUGCUA